AGUCCGCCCGGCUCGGCUGGCCGCAGAAAGGGCCUGGGCGGCCGCACUGAGAGCUUUACGCCCGGAGGCGUCGGCGCUGCCACUGGCCCGCGACGGGAACGGGGCGAAAAGGCGGCGGCACCAUGUUCUCCCUCAAGCCGCCCAAACCCACCUUCAGGUCCUACCUCCUGCCACCGCCCCAGACUGACGAUAAGAUCAAUUCGGAACCGAAGAUUAAAAAACUGGAGCCAGUCCUUUUGCCAGGAGAAAUUGUCGUAAAUGAAGUCAAUUUUGUGAGAAAAUGCAUUGCAACAGACACAAGCCAGUACGAUUUGUGGGGAAAGCUGAUAUGCAGUAACUUCAAAAUCUCCUUUAUUACAGAUGACCCAAUGCCAUUACAGAAAUUCCAUUACAGAAACCUUCUUCUUGGUGAACACGAUGUCCCUUUAACAUGUAUUGAGCAAAUUGUCACAGUAAACGACCACAAGAGGAAGCAGAAAGUCCUAGGCCCCAACCAGAAACUGAAAUUUAAUCCAACAGAGUUAAUUAUUUAUUGUAAAGAUUUCAGAAUUGUCAGAUUUCGCUUUGAUGAAUCAGGUCCCGAAAGUGCUAAAAAGGUAUGCCUUGCAAUAGCUCAUUAUUCCCAGCCAACAGACCUCCAGCUACUCUUUGCAUUUGAAUAUGUUGGGAAAAAAUACCACAAUUCAGCAAACAAAAUUAAUGGAAUUCCCUCAGGAGAUGGAGGAGGAGGAGGAGGAGGAGGUAAUGGAGCUGGUGGUGGCAGCAGCCAGAAAACUCCACUCUUUGAAACUUACUCGGAUUGGGACAGAGAAAUCAAGAGGACAGGUGCUUCCGGGUGGAGAGUUUGUUCUAUUAACGAGGGUUACAUGAUAUCCACUUGCCUUCCAGAAUACAUUGUAGUGCCAAGUUCUUUAGCAGACCAAGAUCUAAAGAUCUUUUCCCAUUCUUUUGUUGGGAGAAGGAUGCCACUCUGGUGCUGGAGCCACUCUAACGGCAGUGCUCUUGUGCGAAUGGCCCUCAUCAAAGACGUGCUGCAGCAGAGGAAGAUUGACCAGAGGAUUUGUAAUGCAAUAACUAAAAGUCACCCACAGAGAAGUGAUGUUUACAAAUCAGAUUUGGAUAAGACCUUGCCUAAUAUUCAAGAAGUACAGGCAGCAUUUGUAAAACUGAAGCAGCUAUGCGUUAAUGAGCCUUUUGAAGAAACUGAAGAGAAAUGGUUAUCUUCACUGGAAAAUACUCGAUGGUUAGAAUAUGUAAGGGCAUUCCUUAAGCAUUCAGCAGAACUUGUAUACAUGCUAGAAAGCAAACAUCUCUCUGUAGUCCUACAAGAGGAGGAAGGAAGAGACUUGAGCUGUUGUGUAGCUUCUCUUGUUCAAGUGAUGCUGGAUCCCUAUUUUAGGACAAUUACUGGAUUUCAGAGUCUGAUACAGAAGGAGUGGGUCAUGGCAGGAUAUCAGUUUCUAGACAGAUGCAACCAUCUAAAGAGAUCAGAGAAAGAGUCUCCUUUAUUUUUGCUAUUCUUGGAUGCCACCUGGCAGCUGUUAGAACAAUAUCCUGCAGCUUUUGAGUUCUCCGAAACCUACCUGGCAGUGUUGUAUGACAGCACCCGGAUCUCACUGUUUGGCACCUUCCUGUUCAACUCCCCUCACCAGCGAGUGAAGCAAAGCACGGUCAGUAGGAUAAAAAGUUGUACAAAACAAGAUUAUUUUCCUUCACGAGUUUGAAGUUUCUGGUCACAAUUCAUUGAUGUAGAGGAUUUAUGACUAAGCAGGGUCUCAAGCCAAACUUGAAACCAUUCUGAACCAAAGUGCCAUUUCACCCACCUCGAACCAACAACAGAAGCUGACAAAUGCCGUGGAGACCAUUGAGAGAAACAGAAAGGGGCAGCUCUUGUGGACCUUCAGGAAGCCUUUCUAGGAAGAGGAUUGCCCUCAUAGUGAGCUCCGGGGUCUUCAGCCUCAGCCGUAAGGCCCUGGGCUAGGCAGUGUGACCUAGGGAGCGGGAAACCUGAGUUCUGGCCCUGGUCUGGGAAAAGUGCUAGGCCCAUGUUCCACUCAGGCUUCAGCCUGAGAGUCCAGGUUGCUAACCUGUAAAAUGGAUCUGUCAAACUAACACUUAUGCCUUUAGUCUCAUUGUAUGAGGUGAAACAUUUUGUAAACUGUGAAUCAUUAUGCAAAUUUUCCUAAAGACAUAUGAAUUAUUCUGGAUUUGUUGGUAUAAAAGACAAAACACACUGGUCAGUUAAGGAGCUGAUUUUAUUUAGGCUAUUGCAGGAGGGAGAACUUAAUUAAUGGGCAUCCCAAAGAAAAGGACAAGGCCUGGGAUUUUAUAGUCAGAAGACAGGGGAAUCAGGAGGGAGGGCAGUCUCAGUCCACAGGAGCCAGUUCUCAGGACACAAAAGGCAGGAGAGAUUGUCCAGCAUUGCCACUUUUGGGGAACCCAGGGCUCAAAGAAACUCAACACCGUCAGCCUGUCUCUACAAAAAAUACAAAAAUUAGCCAGACAUGGUGGUGCGCACCUGUGGUCCCAGCUACUGGGGAGGCUGAGGUGGGAGGAUGGCUUAAGCCCAGGAGGCAGAGAUUGCAGUGAGCUGAGACUGUGCCACUGCACUCCAGCCUGGGUGAUAGAGCCAGAGUCUGUCCCCUGCCCACCCCACCAGGAAAGUUUGACCUUUCCAGAUACUGUGCUGAGAACCAGUGAUACAGGCUUAGAGGCUCCUGAGGCAUGGAACGCUCAUUUGUUCCUAAAAUACAUGCUCUCCCAGUUGCUUGUUUUUAUUUUUCGUCACCAUAAUCAUUCUUGGGGCCCCUCUCUGCCUCGAGCUAGGCUUUCCCCCUGGCCUUGUUUGCCUCCUUCAGCUCUUCCCCAUUGUCUCCCGUCACUACCCCGUGCGCACACAGUGUGAGCCUGCAAAAGGUGCGUGAGGCGAGGACAAAGACUUUGGGGUCUGGGGACUGGGCAGUGCAUGGGUGGGUAUCUGCGUGGAGGACUCCCAGCCCCCAGACACCACUGCCUCUGCUGCUUGGCUGAUGCUGUGUGUGCGGACAGACUUCUCACCAGGAAUGAACAUUACUGAAUUGUAUUGAGGGAGCUGUAAAAAAUACUUUCUACAAGUAUUUCCUCUGCUUUCCCUGUUCAUGUUCUAGUGCUCUUUUUAAUUUGGCUCUUUCAAAAGCCUUUUCUGACAAAUACUAACAUGAAUCCCCCUCUCCCUUCCUCCCUAGCAGGAACUGGUCAUUGUCUAAGGGUCGUGAUUCUUAACCGUUCUCAGCCCCUUCCACACAGGCAAAAGCCCAAAGCAUUUCUUCCUUUUUUUUCCAUUCUGAGGCCACCUUAGGUGCUAGUGGCCAGGUAGUGUUUAUAGAAAAUCUGGUCUCUCUUGGGAUAAAUAUUUUUAAUUUUUACCUUUUAAAAAAGAGAACAUCUUUUUUUUUUUUUUUAAGACAGUUUGGCUCUGUCACCCAGGCUGGAGUACAGUGGUACAAUAUCAGCUCACUGCAACCUCUGCCUCCUGGGUCCAAGCACUGCUCUCGCCUCAACCACCUGAGUAGCUAGGACUGCAGGCGCAUGCCACCACGCCUAGCUAAUUUUUGUAUUUUUUUGUAGAGUCAGGGUUUCGCCAUGUUGCCCAGUCUGGUCUUGAACUCCUGGACUCAAGCAAUCCGCCCACCUCAGCUUCCCAAAGUACUGGGAUUACAGGCGUGAGCCACCGUGCUUGGCCAAGAGGACAUUUUCUAUAUACUUACUGAAGGGCCAUUAAAACACGUUUGGGUUCAUGUUUUACUAGAUUUCAGCUCUUAACAGUGUUUGAAGCAAAUGGAUUGUUUUUAAUCCAUGUACAUGAUGAAAUGUCAAGUAACUAAAAUUUUUUUUUUUUUUUUUUUGAGACAGAGUCUUGCUCUAUCACCCAGGCUGGAGCACAGUGGCAUGAUCUCGGCUCACUGCAACCUCUGCCUUCCAGGUUCAGGUGAUUCUCCUGCCACAGCCUCCCGAGUAGCUGGGACUACAGGUGCACACCACCAUGCCUGGCUAAUUUUUGUAUUUUUAGUAGAGACGGGGUUUCACCAUAUUGGCCAGGCUGGUCUUGAACUCCUGACCUCGUGAUCCGCCUGCCUUCGGCCUCCCAAAGUGCUGGGAUUACAGGCAUGAGUCACCACUGCGCCUGGCCAAAACUGUUAAGAGUAUGUGUAUUUGGUGCUUAAUGAAUUUUUACUUAUUUGAAAUAGAAAAUUUUGUAAAACUUUACAAAAUGCCCUGUGCUGUUACACAGCUUAGCCAUUUCUUGAUGAUUCAAGCCGCCACUGUGCCAGGGAAUGCCACCUGGCUGUGAUGUAGUCAUGGCCUCCUGACUGCUAUAUUCUUGUCCUAAUAACAUUCAUUGUUUGCCUUUUUAAUAAUUUCCAAAUAAAUUCUUGGGGGUUUUUUUUUGGUAGAAAAUUUGGAGAGUACUGAAAGGUACAGAACAAAGAAUCAGACAUUUCCCAUCAUCCAGCGACUUUGUGUCUGGAGUUAUUUCCUCCAGCGAACUGUUGUGUAUACACUGCUGUGGUAGCCUGCUGCCAUCAAUCAGCUGAGAUGAGAGUCCUUUCUCCACAUUGCUAAAUGUGACUGUGCUUCAUAGAAAUGGUCUGGGCUGCCUUCCAGAGGAGCUCCAUGUCUUCCUCACAAUGCGGUGGUUGGCUGUCACCCUGUAGCCUUGUGUUGCCUCAGUUUACUGUGGUGGGAAGCCAGAUAACUAGGCUGCACCCGCCCAGAGUCCGGGCUAGAGGUGGACUCCUGUGAAGGAGGGGUCUCCUGUGUACAUGGUCUCCAUGGUUUUAGCCACAUGCUAGGACCACAGGGAGUUGAUCCCUUCCUUCCUACCCUGAGUCUGUGGUCUGUGAUUUGAGAUCACUGGCUCAGUGAAGUGUAGCUCCCCACUUACGAAGUAAGUUAUAAAAUUGGUGGCAGUGAUUUCCAUCCAAAGAUUUUGUUAAUCCACUUACCAACAGGUAACUACUUAAAUGUACUGACCGUGUGCUCAUAAAAGUAAAAUACUGUAAUUAUAGAAAUAAAUUCAACAUGUUUAAGACUU